GUGCCAAGGGGAUCUCAGCUGGUUCACAUUCUGAGACUGUGUUCUGGAAUGUGCUGCCCUUUCAGCUUAGAGAGAGGAGUUUGGGUCUUUUUGGGAUAAAGCCUGCCUUGUGGGAGAAGAAAGGGAGAGUAACGCUUUGCAUGUGGAAAAUACUUCAACGUGGUUUUGCAUCUGUGUGUUUAAACUUCAAACAACCGCCCUGCGGUGGAAGCACACCUCCUCCCUGAAGGUGGCCAACGAGCCCGUCUUAGCCUUCACGCAGGGCAGCCCUGAGCGAGAUGCCCUGCAAAAGGCCUUGAAGGACCUGAAGGGCCGGAUGGAAGCCAUCCCAUGCGUGGUGGGGGAUGAGGAGGUGUGGACGUCGGACGUGCAGUACCAAGUGUCGCCUUUUAACCAUGGACAUAAGGUGGCCAAGUUCUGUUAUGCAGACAAGAGCCUGCUCAACAAAGCCAUUGAGGCUGCCCUGGCUGCCCGGAAAGAGUGGGACCUGAAGCCUAUUGCAGACCGGGCCCAGAUCUUCCUGAAGGCGGCAGACAUGCUGAGUGGGCCGCGCAGGGCUGAGAUCCUCGCCAAGACCAUGGUGGGACAGGGUAAGACCGUGAUCCAAGCGGAGAUUGACGCUGCAGCGGAACUCAUCGACUUCUUCCGGUUCAAUGCCAAGUAUGCGGUGGAGCUGGAGGGGCAGCAGCCCAUCAGCGUGCCCCCGAGCACCAACAGCACGGUGUACCGGGGUCUGGAGGGCUUCGUGGCGGCCAUCUCGCCCUUUAACUUCACUGCAAUCGGCGGCAACCUGGCGGGGGCACCGGCCCUGAUGGGCAACGUGGUCCUAUGGAAGCCCAGUGACACUGCCAUGCUGGCCAGCUAUGCUGUCUACCGCAUCCUUCGGGAGGCUGGCCUGCCCCCCAACAUCAUCCAGUUUGUGCCAGCUGAUGGGCCCCUAUUUGGGGACACUGUCACCAGCUCAGAGCACCUCUGUGGCAUCAACUUCACAGGCAGUGUGCCCACCUUCAAACACCUGUGGAAGCAGGUGGCCCAGAACCUGGACCGGUUCCACACCUUCCCACGCCUGGCUGGAGAGUGCGGCGGAAAGAACUUCCACUUCGUGCACCGCUCGGCCGACGUGGAGAGCGUGGUGAGCGGGACCCUCCGCUCAGCCUUCGAGUACGGUGGCCAGAAGUGUUCCGCGUGCUCGCGUCUCUACGUGCCGCACUCGCUGUGGCCGCAGAUCAAAGGGCGGCUGCUGGAGGAGCACAGUCGGAUCAAAGUGGGCGACCCUGCAGAGGAUUUUGGGACCUUCUUCUCUGCAGUGAUUGAUGCCAAGUCCUUUGCCCGUAUCAAGAAGUGGCUGGAGCACGCACGCUCCUCACCCAGCCUCACCAUCCUGGCCGGGGGCAAGUGUGAUGACUCCGUGGGCUACUUUGUGGAGCCCUGCAUCGUGGAGAGCAAGGACCCUCAGGAGCCCAUCAUGAAGGAGGAGAUCUUCGGGCCUGUACUGUCUGUGUACGUCUACCCGGAUGACAAGUACAAGGAGACGCUGCAGCUGGUUGACAGCACCACCAGCUAUGGCCUCACGGGGGCAGUGUUCUCCCAGGAUAAGGACGUCGUGCAGGAGGCCACAAAGGUGCUGAGGAAUGCUGCCGGCAACUUCUACAUCAACGACAAGUCCACUGGCUCGAUAGUGGGCCAGCAGCCCUUUGGGGGGGCCCGAGCCUCUGGAACCAAUGACAAGCCAGGGGGCCCACACUACAUCCUGCGCUGGACGUCGCCGCAGGUCAUCAAGGAGACACAUAAGCCCCUGGGGGACUGGAGCUACGCGUACAUGCAGUGAGCCCCUCUCGGGCUCCACCGUCCAGCUGUCUGUCCGUCCAGGUGGCCGACCUCACUGCACAGACCCCACUCCAGCCCCUCCACCCCUUCUUCAUGCACAGCUGCCUUUCUAUAAUCCGGGCUUGACUCCCUUCUUACCACUGUAUUCUGGCCUCUCCCAUGCCUCAGGCUCUGGUUUGAGAUCGUGCUGGGGAGGAACAUGGCCACUACCCCUUAUCCCAUCGGCCAUGUGGGAGGUAUGACCCUGGUGCCUGGCAGGUUCUCCCUCUGCCCUCCACUGGGCCCAGUGGCUCAGGGACCUGGGGAAAGGAGAUGGAGCAGCUCUUGGGAUCCUUUGGGGAAAAGGAGGCCAUUCUGGGCCCCUUGGCAAACCUCACCACUCACAGAGGCUCCUGGCCUUGAUCCCUGCCCCUCCAGGUGUCCAGGGUAAAGUGUAACUCAGACUGACCUGUGGGGCACAGGGGGCACCAGCUGGCCUUGCCCUCUCUGGUCUGGGCUGUCUACCUUCCUCACUGUAUCUUUGCCCAGACCCACCUGGGCCAGUAGGCCCCUGUCCCCAGCCACACACCUUAGAUGCUGGCAUGCCUUACUCCAGGUGCCUGUGUUUGGCCGAGGCCUGUGUGAUUCCCGGUCUGCACCACAUGGCGGGGUUGGGGGGCCGCUGGAGGCCACCUGCCAAGGCGUGGGAUGGGAUGGUCCUGCCGGUUUAGGCCGUGAUUCUGGAAAACCUUGGAUGGGCCUUCGUCCUAUGUCAGCCUUCCCUUUGAUCCUCAGGCCCUACCUGUAGAGACCUCCACUCCUAGAGCCAGUCUCAGGGUCUGGGAUUUCCCUGCAGGAGCUCAGCCACCACUGUGCCAUGGUGACACAGGCCAAGGCAGACAUUGGCCCUCCCUUCUCCCAGCCCCCAGAGGCCUGGCCUUGGGUUCGUCAGCAUGGGCCGAGGACGUUGCCUGUAGAAUCCUCCUCUGCCUGGGAGUGGCUCUGUGUGGACCAGUCCCUCACUGGCCCAUUCUUUUUUUGACGCAGCCAAUCUGUGACCACGAUUCCUCCCACAGAUGCCUCCUGCUUGGAUUCUGAGUGGUCAGAGAUCUGUAAAGCAUGACUUUCAAGGAUGGUUCUUAGGGGACUGUGAAAGUGUUGGGUCUUCCUCCAGGAUGCCUGCAUGGGACCCCACCCGGAGCUGGUGUGGCCAUUCCCCAAGUGCCACUGGCCCAUGGAUGGGGGUGGGUGCUGGUGCCAGCUGGGCUGGGUGUGGGUUCUGUGUCCUUCCAGGAUAUGUGUCAUUUCCCAUGAGGGGCCGGGGCAGGUGGCUGGGUGGGGGCACAGGCUGGAGUAUUCUUAGUUCUACUGGUUCUACACUGUGAGGUGGCAAUGGGAUUUGCUCAGAUGCCACCCAAUAAAAUGCCUGUUACUUAA